CUCUUCCUCCUCGCGGUCGCGGCCGGACGGAGGGUGGAGGGCCCUGCGCCUGCGCGGAGCUGGAGUCCGGCUGGGCCGCAGCCGCUGGGAGACCGGCGGUUGCCGUGGGGACCGGUCGGGCCCCUCCCUCCUCCGGUCCCCCGCCCCAGGUCCUUCCCCACCGAGACGCGCCGGCGGACCGCGGGCGAGUGCAGCCGGUGACCCGGCGAGAGGCGGCGCCGCUCCCAAGAUGUCGCAGACGGCCAUGUCCGAAACCUACGAUUUUUUGUUUAAGUUCUUGGUUAUUGGAAAUGCAGGAACUGGCAAAUCUUGCUUACUUCAUCAGUUUAUUGAAAAAAAAUUCAAAGAUGACUCAAAUCAUACAAUAGGAGUGGAAUUUGGUUCAAAGAUAAUAAAUGUUGGUGGUAAAUAUGUAAAGUUACAAAUAUGGGAUACAGCAGGACAAGAACGAUUCAGGUCCGUGACGAGAAGUUAUUACCGAGGCGCGGCCGGGGCUCUCCUCGUCUAUGAUAUCACCAGCCGAGAAACCUACAAUGCGCUUACUAAUUGGUUAACAGAUGCCCGAAUGCUAGCGAGCCAGAACAUUGUGAUCAUCCUUUGUGGAAACAAGAAGGACCUGGAUGCAGAUCGUGAAGUUACCUUCUUAGAAGCCUCCAGAUUUGCUCAAGAAAAUGAGCUGAUGUUUUUGGAAACAAGUGCGCUCACAGGGGAGAAUGUAGAAGAGGCUUUUGUACAGUGUGCAAGAAAAAUACUUAACAAAAUCGAAUCAGGUGAGCUGGACCCAGAAAGAAUGGGCUCAGGUAUUCAGUACGGAGAUGCUGCCUUGAGACAGCUGAGGUCACCGCGGCGCGCACAGGCCCCGAACGCUCAGGAGUGUGGUUGUUAGGAGAGCACACAGGUGUUCAUACAGUGGCAUUUGGGACACAAUCGUUGGAACCUGAAGAAUCUGAAGUUUUUUUUACCACCAUCUUUUUCUACUCUGUAUGGAAGUAGAUCUUUAUGGGGAAAAGAGAAUUUGGGGUGUUCUGCAAGCCAGUCAAAGUGGCACAGCAAAUCAUAUAAAUCGAAUUAAAUGGACAACACCGUUAGAUGUGUAUGUAAAAAUUUUCUGUUUCAUAUUUUUCCUUUCACUUUCGGUUUAAAACAUGCUAUAUGUACUGUAUGUCCUGUAGCCCAGUGCGGCUCCACAGCAUGGAAUCUGAUGUAUGAUAUGAUAGAAUGUGGCACUAAAUGCAGUUUCAGAUUUUAUUUUUUUUAAUCAUAUGAACUAAAAUUGUCAAUUGUGAGGUGUGCUUUUCUCAUCAUGUUGGUUAUAUUGCACAAUUGGUUAUAUUUAUGACCUGAUAUUCAAAGACUCUGGCAUUGAUAGCCAGUGUGUUUUCUUAUUUAACUCCGUUUACUACAUUCUACAUGGUGUUUACGUGAUCCACACUUGAAAUACUAGAUCAGUAGACAUUCACUAAUAUACCAAAAUAAAAUGAAAAAUUGAGUUUUUCCGUGAACUUUAUACUGUCCAGCUCUGUUGAUUUUAAAGCCUCUUCAUCCAGGUCAGUUCAGGAAGUAUAUCUGGAGUACCUGCUCUGUUUUUGGCUGUGAGACUAGCACUAAGGAUUCUGGUACCUUUACCCAAACCUACUGGGCUACUAAUACUUCUCUCAGCAGUUGAUCAAAUACAAUAGACCAUGUAAGCUGGGGCCGCUCAUCCACUUCCAGUUUGCUGGUCUCCCUGCUAGAAAACACAUUGUACUGUGCUUUUUCUGGAAUUCAGUAUAAUGGCAUCACUGCCUGUUUUUCACAUCUUUUGUUUCCUGUUCAUUUUAAGGAAACCUACUAAAUCCAGUUAAUAUUAAAUGGACACCACUCAUUAAGAAAUUUCUUUAUGGCUUCUGCUGAAUACUUAAAUGCCUUACUACAGUUAUCCAGUUGACAUGUUUUUAAUUCAUAUAAGGUAUAUUGGGUAUAUUGAAGUAUAUAUUGUAUUACAAAGACUUGUUCUUGUAUUUUAAAAUGUCAGUGCAAAAAAUAUAUGGUGGAACCUUUCUUUAAAGUUGAAAUGCAGUAUUAUUUAAAUCUGAAAGGUUAAAAAGCUUUCUUCACCUUAUAUAUGUUCUUCCACUGUGACUUUUUAGUUGAAGACUAGUAAAUUAACUUUUAGUUAGAAGAUGCCUACUGCUUUUGUUGUUUAUUUUAAUCAGCAGAGCACAGAGACACAUAAAAACUCUGGGAAAUGACUAGGAUAAAAAUAUCAGUAUGUAUCUGUUUUAGAUAUUUUGAGUUUUGCUUUUUUUAUGCCUUGAAUAUUUUAUUUCAAAAAGUAUCUGAAGCAAAUUCUCAGACUGAACUACUUCUUAGACCUCACUGUAAGAAUAUUUUAUUCAAUGUCUCAUUUAUGAUAGAUUUGCAAGCUGCUCAUUUUUGAACAGCUUUUUGCAUGGGAUAGGAGCAUGUCUAUUCUAACACAUCAGCUUAUUCAAAAGCAAGAAUUUUAAAAAUAAGAUAAAUGUAAAGUUGUUUUAUAAACGAUCCUGUUAAUUAAACCACAGACACCAUAUAUCCUUCUGCAUCCUUUGGCCAAUAAAAGUUGCUGGAGAACCAAACCAUGGUGGUUCUUAAUCAGGCUUUGCCUUUAGGGAGAAUGAGGAGGAGAGAUAAUUGGGUAUUGUUCAGGCUAGUAAUAAAUGUCAUGUUUCUAUUUCCCGCAACUCAUUAAGUUUUCAGGAAGCUCUUAAUUUAGAUUUCUAGGAAAGUAAUUAUUCAGUCUUCCUAGAAAAAGAUUAUAAAGACCAUUUAAACUGGAGAUUGUAAUUUAUUCUUUUACAGUCCAGCAUUUAAGUGAAAAUGAGAACAUCACAAUUUGGGAAUCUGUAAUGGUUUUGUUGAAAACAUUACUUGUGGCUUGUAUAAGAGUGGCUGAAUUCAAGAACAUUGAUUCUUAGCAGAUCAAUAAUAGUAUUUAAAGAAUCUGAUGCUAAAAUUAGAAACCUAAA